GCCCGCUUCUCGCUGGAGUGCGCACCGAGCGGCAGUGACUUCGCCGCUGCUGUAGUUCCCCGGCUGGAUGCGGUGACUGGUGCCAGUGCUCAGGCGCCCGCUGCCCUUGACCUCCCGCCCCGCGAGCCCUAACUCAGCGCAGGAGGACCGGCUGCCGCCGCCGCCGCCGCCAGGUAGACCAGGCCUGGCUGGGUUAGGCCAGAAGGGUGUCCCUGGCGCAGGUCUCCCGCGGAGGGCAGAACUAGAACCAGGUUCCCGGCCGUUUCCGACCACACGGAUGGGGCGGACCCAUCAGAGCCAAGCACAGUGGGAACUUUCAGAAAGCACUGGUUGAAGGAACGCUGGAAUCCCUGGGACUUACUGCGUAGCAUGUAGUAGUUGCUCCUCUACAAAAGUUUCACCUUAUGAAGUAUAGCAGGCUCUGAUGCUGGUGUCUGGUAGAAGAAGAUUACUCACAGCUCUGCUGCAGGCUCAGAAGUGGCCCUUUCAACCCUCCAGAGACAUGAGACUAGUGCAGUUCCGGGCACCCCACCUGGUGGGGCCUCACUUGGGCCUGGAGACAGGGAAUGGUGGAGGGGUUAUCAACCUCAAUGCCUUUGACCCCACACUCCCAAAGACGAUGACGCAGUUCCUAGAGCAGGGAGAGGCCACCCUCUCAGUGGCAAGAAGAGCCUUGGCUGCCCAGUUGCCAGUCCUACCAUGGUCGGAGGUAACCUUCCUGGCUCCAGUCACAUGGCCAGAUAAGGUGGUGUGUGUGGGCAUGAAUUAUGUGGACCACUGCAAAGAACAGAACGUGCCCGUGCCCAAGGAGCCCAUCAUCUUCAGCAAGUUUGCCAGCUCCAUCGUGGGGCCCUAUGAUGAGGUGGUCCUCCCACCACAGAGCCAGGAGGUAGAUUGGGAAGUGGAGCUGGCCGUGGUCAUUGGAAAGAAAGGCAAGCACAUCAAGGCCACAGAUGCCAUGGCCCACGUGGCCGGCUUCACUGUGGCUCAUGACGUGAGUGCUCGUGACUGGCUAACAAGACGCAAUGGGAAACAGUGGCUGCUGGGAAAAACCUUCGACACCUUCUGCCCUCUGGGCCCUGCCUUGGUGACCAAGGACAGUGUAGCAGAUCCACACAACUUAAAGAUCUGCUGCCGAGUGAAUGGGGAAGUCGUCCAGAGCAGCAACACCAACCAGAUGGUAUUCAAGACAGAGGACCUGAUAGCCUGGGUCUCCCAGUUUGUUACCUUUUACCCAGGGGAUGUCAUCCUAACUGGGACCCCCCCAGGUGUCGGUGUAUUCAGGAAACCUCCUGUCUUUCUCAAGGUCUCUGAAGGUCCAGAUAGCACUGAUGGCAAGCUUUGGGUCCGCACACUCUGGAAAGAAGAGAGAAGUGAAGGCUCUAGGGGGCAGCAGCCACCAGCAAACACCACUGCCUGCAGGAGCCUGGGCUGACUGGUUGAGACUCACCGAAGAUCCCUUCUUCCUGGGCGGUGGCCUGCAGGAACUGGAACAGCUGGUCUGUGUAGCCCGACUCUGCAGAAGAGAGAAGACCUAGACCUGGCACCCAGCACAGACACAGCCUGCCUCGAGGACUGCAAGGGAACAAGGGCCUCACCAGUAUCGGGCAGCUGGCCCUGGCGGAGGAAGGCGGCAGCCUGUGCAAAGGCCUUGAGCAGCGGGCUGAGCAGGCGGCAGAGGAAAAGAAAGAAAUCUGGGCAGUGUGACUGCUGGCUGAGCUGGAGGGGACAGGCCGGGGUGAGUGCAGCUCCCCACCACCUCCCUACCACCUCCCUCCAGGGGCAGCUUUUUGAAACACACCCUGGAGUACUGGCCCUCGGUCUCUUUGAAGUCAUCACUGUCACUAUCAGUAAAAUCCCCACUCGGUUUCCACAGCAGCUUUCUGCUCAGUCGCCGUUGCCCUGUGUCACAGGCUGGCCGGACCCGGAGCCAUUGUUCUCUGACAAGCUGGCCAGGGAUCAACCCUACACCCCCAGACCAGGUACAUGCAGGUGAAACCAGUAAAAGCAGACCUAGAGACCCAAGAGGAUGGCCAGAGCCAUGCCCCAGCACCUGCUGGGCCAACUUGCAGAGUGAGAGGAAGUGAAUUCCCACCCUCAAGGGCAGUAGCCCUGUGGCCAAGAAAUGUGGGGAGCAGGAGGUGUGCAGAGAACCUCAGAGGCACACAUGUCCAGUGCUAUCCAGAGAGACACACACAGAACCGGGGCAUAGGUGGCCAUAUCCCAAGGCACAGGGAGCAGAGGUGCGAGCUAGGCUUCCCCGCUGCAAGGCCAGGGGCUGCCCACCCCCACAGCACACACAGGGCAGAGGAGGAGCCUGGGGCAGCUGGCACUCAGGGUGGGAGGCUGGAGGAGGCCAGGCUCCAGGCAAGGAUCUUGUCUCCAACUGCCCUGCCUACCUCCUCAGCAACCAGGAGCCCGCAUUGGAUGAGCCUGUCCAGCACCUCCUGACAGUAGCAGUAGGAAGACUGGCAGGGCUGGGAGAAAAAGGCACCCAUGUGGCCUCAGGAGAGCCAGGCACAUGGGCAGGGGCCUAGCCAAAGACCGGGCAAGGCCAGACCUACCACCCAGGAGGUUUCAGAGGUAGAGCAUGGGCAGGGAUGGGCCAUUCCUACCACCAAGAGGGGAAGGCCUAGGACCAAGUGGGCCGUAGGGGAGGCCUGACCUUUAGCAGCAGCAGGUCUUGCGGCAGCAGGUGCAUCAGCAGCAGGAUCUGGCGGUACAGCUCAUUCUGGCUCAGCAGCAAUAUGCCCUGCAGCUCCCAGGGCCCCUGGGGCGGCACUCUGCCUGCCAGCAGCCCCCGCACUGCACAGGCUGGGGGCGGAGGGUCCAUUAUGAGGAAGGAGCCGUUCCCUUCACCACUGCACACACAUCCCACCUCGGCCUCCAGAAGUGCUGGGAUCACAGGCAUGAGGCACCGCGCCCAGCCCCCAAAGCUUCUUAAGCUGAUAAGCAACUUCAGCAAAGUCUCAAGUUACAAAAUUAAUGUGCAAAAAUUGUUAUAGCAUUUCUAUACACCAACAACAAUCGAGCUGAGAGCCAGAUCAUGAGUGAGCUCCCACUCACAAUUGCUACAAGAAGAAUAAGGUACCUGGCAAUUCAGGUAACAAGGGAAGUGAAGGACCUUUACAAAGAGAACAACAAACCACUGCUCAAAGAAAUCAGAGAGGAUACAAAUGGAAAAACAUUCCAUGCUCAUGUAUAGGGAGAAUCAAUAUUAUGAAAAUGGCCAUACUGCCCAAAGUAAUUUAUUGAUCCAAUGCUAUUCCCAUUAAACUACCAUGGAAGUUCUUCACAGAAAUAGAAAAAAAAAUAUUUUAAAAUUCAUGUGGAACCCAAAGAGAGCCUGAAGAGCCAAGGCAAUUCUCAGCAAAAAGAAAAAUCUGGAGGCAUCAUGCUCUUCAACUUCAAACUAUACUACAGGUCUACAGUAACCAAAGCAGCAUGGCACUGGUGCAAGAAAAGACACAUAGACCAAUGGAACAGAAUAGAGAACCCAGAAAUAAGACUACACCCCCACAGCAAUCCGAUAUUUGACAAACCUGACAAAAACAAGCAAUGGAGAAAGGAUUCUCUAAUAAAUGGUGCUGGGAAAGCUGGCUAGCCAUAUGUGCAAAUUGAAACUGGACUCCAGCCUCACACCUAAUAAAAAAAUCAGCUGAAGAUGAAUUAAAGACUUAAAUGUAAAACCCCAAACUAUAAAAAUCCUAGAAGAAAGCCUAGGCAAUACCAUUCGGAACAUAGACAUGGGCAAAGAUUUCAUGACAAAGAUGCCAAAAGCAAUCGCAACAAAAGCCAAAAUUGACAAAUGGGAUCUAAUUAAACUAAAGAGUUUCCACACAGCAAAAGAAACUAACAGCAGAGUAAACAGACAACCUAAAGAAUGAGAGAAAAGUUUUGCAAACUAUGCAUCUAACAAAGGUCUAAUAUCUAGCAUCUGUAAGAAACUUGGCUGGGCAUGGUGGCUCACACCUGUAAUCACAGCACUGUGGGAGGCCAAGGCAGGAGGAUCACCUGAGGUCAGAAGUUCAAGACCAGCCUGGCCAACAUGAUGAAACCACAUCUCUAGUCAAAAUAUAAACAUUAGCUGGGCGUGGUGGUGCAUGCCUGUACUCCCAGCUACUCGGGAGGCUGAGGCAGAAGAAUUGCUUGAACCCAGGAGGUGGAGGUUGCCGUGAGCCGAGAUUGCACCACAGCACUCCAGCCUGGGCAAAAGAGUGAGACUCCGUCUCAAAAAAAAAAAGAAAAGAAAAGAAAAAAUAAAAUAAAAAAGAAAUUUAAACAAAUUCAAAACAACCCCACUAAAAAGUGGGCAAAGGACAUGAAAAGACACUUUUCAAAAGAAGACAUACAUGCAGCCAACAAUCAUAUGAAAAAAAGCUCAACAUCACUGAUCAGUAGAGAAAUGCAAAUUAAAAACCACAGUGAGAUACUAUCUCACACCAGUCAGAAUGGUGAUUAUUAAAAAGUCCAAAAAUAACAGGUGCUGGCAAGGUUAUGGAGAAAAAGGAGCACUUUUAUACUGUUGAUGGGAAUAUAAAUUAGUUCAACCAUUGUGGAAAACAGUGUGAUGAUUCCUCAAAGACCUAGAGAAAUAAAUAACAUUCACCCAAGCAAUCUUAUUACUGGGUAUAUAACCAAAGGAAUGUAAAUCAUUCUAUUAUAAAGACACAUGCAUGCAUGCGUCCAUUGCAGCACUAUUCACAAUAGCACAGAUGUGGAAUCAAUCUAAAUGCCCAUCAAUGAUAGACUGGAUAAAGAAAAUGUGGUAUAUAUACACCACGAAAUACUAUGCAGUUAUAAAAAGUAAGAAUAAGAUCACGACCUUUGCAGGGACAUGGAUGGAGCUGGAGGCCAUUAUCCUUAGCAAACUAAUGCAGGAACAGAAAUCCAAAUAUUAUACCACAUGUUCUUACUUAUAAGUGGGAGCUAAAUGAUGAGAACAUAUGGACGCAAAGAAAGGAACAAUGCACACUGGGGCCUACCAGAGGAUGGAGGGUGAGGAGGGAGAGCAUCAGGAAAAAUAACUAAUGGAUACUAGGUUUAAUACCUGGGUGAUGAAAUAAUAUGUACAACAAACUCCUAUGACACAUGUUUACCUAUGUAACAAACCUGCACAUCCUGCACAUGUACCCCUGAAUUUAAAAUAAAAGUUUAAAAAAAAGUA